AGCUGUGAGACGACGAGUGCGUGAAGUGAAGGCGAUUGAGAGGGGCUGAGGGAAUUGUCCUCUGUGGAAGGGACUUUCUUUUGGCCCUAGGCCCCUUCCUGCCCCUGUCGUCAGCAGAGUCUCUACAAGGAAGAUAACGGACUGUAAAAUUCUAUAAAGCAAAGCUACACAUCACUUGACACCAUACACCAUCUUGGUUACAUAAUGAAGAGAGAUGGAAAACUUGAUGACUAGCUCCACCCUACCGCCCCUUUUUGCAGAUGAAGACGGUUCCAAGGAGAGUAAUGAUCUGGCUACCACUGGGUUAAAUCACCCAGAGGUUCCAUACAGUAGUGGCGCCACAUCAUCCACCAACAAUCCAGAAUUUGUGGAGGAUCUCUCUCAAGGUCAGUUGCUUCAGAGUGAGUCUUCAAAUGCAGCAGAAGGCAAUGAACAGAGGCAUGAAGAUGAGCAACGAAGUAAACGAGGAGGUUGGUCCAAAGGAAGAAAGAGGAAGAAACCUCUUCGAGACAGCAAUGCACCCAAAUCCCCCCUUACAGGAUAUGUUCGGUUCAUGAAUGAGCGUCGAGAACAACUUCGAGCAAAGAGACCAGAAGUCCCAUUUCCAGAAAUCACAAGGAUGUUAGGCAAUGAAUGGAGUAAACUGCCUCCUGAGGAAAAACAGCGCUACCUUGAUGAAGCAGACAGAGAUAAGGAGCGUUACAUGAAGGAACUGGAACAGUAUCAGAAAACAGAGGCCUACAAGGUCUUCAGUAGGAAAACCCAGGACCGUCAGAAAGGCAAAUCUCAUAGGCAAGAUGCAGCCCGGCAGGCCACUCAUGAUCAUGAGAAAGAAACAGAGGUAAAGGAACGGUCUGUUUUUGACAUCCCUAUAUUUACAGAGGAAUUCUUGAACCAUAGCAAAGCUCGGGAAGCAGAGCUCCGCCAGCUUCGCAAAUCCAACAUGGAGUUUGAGGAGAGGAAUGCAGCCCUGCAAAAGCACGUGGAGAGCAUGCGCACAGCAGUGGAGAAGCUGGAGGUGGAUGUGAUCCAGGAGCGGAGCCGCAACACAGUCUUACAGCAGCACCUGGAGACCCUGCGGCAGGUGCUGACCAGCAGCUUUGCCAGCAUGCCCUUGCCUGGAAGUGGAGAGACACCUACAGUGGACACCAUUGACUCAUAUAUGAACAGACUGCACAGUAUUAUUUUAGCUAAUCCCCAAGACAAUGAAAACUUCAUAGCUACAGUUCGAGAAGUUGUGAACAGACUCGAUCGUUAGGGAAUGGUGAGUGCUCACUGAUAAAUAUUUAUAUGCCAGCACAUCAUCAAAAAUAAGAUGUCAUCAGACUUUAUCAAUACUACUAAAACCCUGGGAUUACAUUGGAUGAACAAGUUGGAGACUUGGUUAAGAUUCCUGUUGCAUGGUUGUUAAAUGUAGUAAAUAAUAUUAGAAAAGAGAAUCACUGUAGUCCCAGCUACUUGGGAGGCUGAGGUGGGAGGAUUGCUUGAGCCCAGCAGUUCAAGUCCAGAGAGAUCCUGUCUCUAAAAAUAAAAGAAAACAGACUCAAGACAGUUUUUUCUUAUGCUUGCUUCAGAAUGGUUUAAUGGGAAAAGCAUGGUUUUUGUGGCUUGACCUCAUUUCUAGCUUUGUCACUUAUUAGCUGUAUUCUUGGGCAUUAGUUUCCCAAAAGGUUUUGAAAAGUGAGUGGGAAACUUAGAAGAAAUCAUCCCCAAAACAGCACUCAGAACAAAAUAAAUAUAACUUAAUUUUUAAUCUUCCUUUUCUCUGGAAAAUACUAAUGAUAAUUUAGAAGUAGUCAGUGAGACAUUGUAUGUAUGUGAGCCUACAUAAGUAGGAAGCUUUUAUAUUCACCACUCAAUAACACAGUGACUGUUGUCUGUUAAAUGUUGAUGUGGACUCACCAUACAAACAGGUAACUCCCUGGUUUUGAUAGAUUAAAAAAUAAACUCUUCAGCCAGGUGCAAUGGCUCACACCUGUAAGCCUAGCAGUUUGGGAGGUCAAGGCAGGCAGAUCGCUGGAGUCCAGGUUCAAGACCAGUCUGGGCAACAUGACAAAACCCCGUAUCUACAAAAAAUACAAAAAAUUAGCCAGGCAUGGUGGUAUGCGCUUGUGGUCCCAGCUGCUUGGGAGGCUAAAGUGGGAGGAUCACUUGGGCUUAGAAGGUCAAGGCGAGGCUGCAGUGAGCCAUUAUCAGACCACUGCAUGCCAGCCUGGGUGACAGAGCAAGACACUGUCUCAAAAAUUUUUUUAAAUAAAAAAUAAAUAAACUCUUGGUGGGGCACAGUGGCUCACACCUGUAGUCCUAGCACUUUGGGAGGUUGAGGCAGUAUUGCCUGAGCCCAGGAGUUCAAGACCAGCUUGGGCAAAAUAGUGAGACCCCUGCUUUAAAAAAAAAUGAAAAAAAUUAGCUGAGCAUGAUGGCGCACACCUAUAGUCCUAGCUACUCAGGAGGCUGAGGCAGGAGGAUCACUUAAUCCCAGGAGUUCAGGUUUCAGUAAGCUAGGGUCACACUAGUGUAUUCUAGCCAGGGUAACAGAGCAAGAUUCUGUCUCAAAAAAAAAAAAAACAAAAUAAAAAUAUAAAAUUCUCAAUAAGCAAAAAAGAGAGAGAAAAUAAGUUUUUAAAAAAUAUGUUCAACAAAUGAGCAGUAGUAUGUAUCCUUUUUUUUUUUUUUUUCCAGAAGAGAUCUACCCAUGACACUUUUUGGUACUAAUGGUCAUUUCUCAAAUGGAAUUGGUAUUUAUUCAUUCAAAUUCCUAGAGAUAGGAUACCCCUUUACUAUGCCAUCCCACAAAACUGGCAUCCCUUUGCUCUAUUGGUUAAGUUAUUCCAUACCUGCAGACAUAUAAACUGUGUGGAAAUUUUAAGAUUAGACUCUACAAUGAGGUGGCCAUAUAUGGAUACUAAAAUAAGAGUCAACAGCAGGAUAUGUUCCUUAGAAUGGUCAUGGGUUUGAAUCUUUAUUUGUCCUGUGAGUACAUGAGCACACUCAUAUACAUAAUUUAUAUUCUGGUUUGGUUUGGACUUUGAGCAACAUAUAUAAAGAUAAAUGCCUAGUAAAGACAAAGGCAGAAGUCUUUAUACUUCUUGGUGAUGCCCUUGGAUGGUAACUGUACAAGGCAAUGCAUUAUAUUUUAGCCUCAGCCAUGCUCUGAUGGGGAAAGGAUUACUAUCCUUCUAGGGAGUAGCCAGAUGGAAUGGACUGUACUUCUUAGAGAUGGCUGGACUCCCUGCAGAAUAAAGAAGUGGCAUUACUGCUGCUGCUUAUGAAGGGAACAGCUUGUAAAUCUAGGCCUGGGAUAUUCAGGAGCUCAUCAUCCUUCCCAUUUUCGUACAGUGUUUUCAAUUAGCACUCUUGUAGGCUUGAAAAGUGAGAGCUGGGAGAAACAGUGUGGAAGAUUGUGAAAGAAAACAUUAAUUGAUAACAUCGUGUCUCUUCACAUAGAUACAGGGCAGCUAAUUAAGUAUUGACCCAAAAGUGGUUUUCCAUUUUGAGCAUUUUGCCAGUAAGACUCUCCUAAAGCUUUUUUCAUCUCAAGAGUAUAAACUAUAUUAUUUGUUUUCUGAUGAGUCUUUGAAAACUUAGAAUAUUACUAUUAUCCUUGAUUUUAACCUACAAAUAUUUUGCCCCUGAAAAAAUAGCUAAAAGUGUGAACUGUUAUAUUACUACAGAUUCUUACAGUCUAGCCAUGCAAACAUAACUAACAAUAGAUGGUUCCCCACACCCCCAAAACUGUCAAAGGAAACAAUUACAAAGACUGUGAUUAAUACUGGUUUGGCCUCAUUAUACAAAUAUGUACAGACAGCGAGGCUGAUGUCCCCAGCACUCAUGAUGCAAUUAAUUACUCUGACAAGAGUUUGGCAAAGUUUUCAUCCACUGUCAGGAGCCAGUGAGUGAAGGGAAGCUAAUGGUCUACAAGUUUCAGAGGAGCAUAUUAGGGACCUUUAGAAAUCUAACAUUUUAUAUAUGAAGAAACUGAAUCCCAGAGAGGAGAAACAUCUUGCUUGAAAAUAUCUGCGUAGAUGAGUACAGAAUCCAAGACUAGAACCACAGAUAUCUAAACUCUCUCAUUCACUGGGUUUCUAAAACAUUGCUCUAAGGAAGAGGUGGAUGGGGGAAGGGGAAAGCACUAAAAAAUCCUGAAAUAGAGCAUUAAGAUACAUAGGAAGUAAACAGAUAAAAAUUGUAAUCCAGGAAUUAUAAUGUUAUAGAAUUUUAGCUCAUUUUAAAAUUAUUUUGAUAAAUAUACAGUGGAAGAAUUACCCUACCUGUCUGUCACCUUUCUUGUAGCUGAGUAGUACCUAGAGACAAGUGGAGCUAGGAGGAGGCCAUGAGGGUGAUUUUAAGUUGAAAGGUGACUACCUUAUAUAAACUAUUAAAAUGCAUAUGUUGCCUGAUUUCAAUGAUAAUAUUUGGCUGUUUGAGUUUAGGGAAAAAAAAUCUUAUGUGACUGUAUUUUUAUUAAUAUGAGAAAUGUUCUUGAUUAUAUGCACAUAAUACAUCUCUAUACAUGCAGAUAUCCUUAGUUAACACUUGAAGAAAAUUGGUUUUGAUUGACCAUACAUUCUUCAGACUAAAGUAGGGUACUCAUUUUCCCUCCUCAGGUUUGUCCCUGAUAGUUGCUUUUCUGUGUUUAGCUGAUGAUUUUCCUACCUCCCAUUGUUGCUGAACUGGAACAGGGCCAUGUUUCUCAUUGAAAUGUUAUGUAAAACAUCUCAAUGAGGUUGCCUGCUUACAGCUUUAUGAGUUCUUCAGUUUACAUACACCCUGCACUCACUUUAACGCUUAUGAAACCAAAGCAUUUUUAAAAUCCAUAGCGCUAACCCCUUCCAUUCAAUACUUACUUUCUUGGUGUUAUUUUCCUUGUUUGUUUUUGUUUUUGUUUUGUUUUGUUUUCCUGAUUCUACAGGUCUUAGAACUCCAAGAUGUUCCAUAAGUGUUUUUACUUGUGAGGAAUGAGAAGCCAUCCAUGGAAAUUUGAACUGAGUGGGGGCAGAGAAAGAGUGCAGAUCCCUUUGCUUGUGAAAGAAUUAUCAGUGAGUGAAAGGCCAUCACCCCAGGAAGCCAAAUGAGGGAGCAGCAACAUGUAUAUGAGCUUCCUAUGGAAUUGUCCUUAUGUGAAGCUUUGAAGGUGUACAGCCACUCUCCCGGGUCUUCAGGUUCCUACCAUUUCCAUUUCUGUUAAAGUGGAUCUGCAUAUCUUCAGCUUACUAGGUGACCCGGAUGCUGACAUCUGCUGCUGCAGAAAGGAAGACUUUUCAUUGUAAUUUCGCUUAGACCCUUUUAUCAGUGGAGCUCCAGUUUUCUUACCUAGCUGUCACUUUUUUAAAUGCCUCUGGGGGUUAUUUUUGCUUUCCUUGGCCCCCACCAAUUUAUACAUCUCCAUUUUCUGACCUCUGGACUAACUGGUUGCUCAGCAAGGUUCUGAAGGAGAGUUUCUUGCAUUGGACAGGCCCAGUCUUCUCCCAUCAUUGCCCUGCUGUGACUCCAAAGAAAGGAGCUUCUUGCUGACAGUGCCCUGUGGAGCAAGGCUGUGUUUCCUACCCCACACGGUGCUCAGUGGGUGCCAGCCCUCAGUGUGGCUUUGUGAUUGCUGCCCUAAAGGAGAAUGCUCUUUCCUUCCUCACUGGUACUGCCUGCUGUUUUCUAAGCAUUGCUCCUGCACAGACAUGGAGUCCCAGCCCCAGCAAGGCUCUUCUGUUCCCAUCUGUUGACAAUGUCUUGUGGAGCAUUUUUGCUGAGGAAAAGGUCACUUGUAAACAGAGGAGAAAGGGAAAGAGUACAAAGCCCUAAGUUUAUUGUAAGUGAAAACUGAGGGAAUUCCUGUCUUCUUUAGGAGUAAUGAUUCAUAGAUCUAGAUAGGUGGAAAUAUCAUUCAAAAUAGUCACUUGAGCUCACAAAAAAAGCAAGGAAGAAUUCUCAUGUCCUUUGUCUUCCUUCUGUAGCCAUUAACUGCUGAAUCCAUGUGAGGAAGACAGGCUUCCCUUCCUUCCCCCUCCUUAGUGAUUUUUUCUUUAACAGCAUAAGUAAAGAGGACUUUCUGGUUCAUUUUUGUUUGUUUUGUUUUGUUUUGUUUUGUUUACAGAUGAGGUCUUCCUGUGUUGCCCAGGCUGGAGUGCGGUGGCUAUUCACAGAUGCUAUCAUAGCACACUACAGCCUACAACUCUUGGGCUCAAGCAUCACGCCUAGCAGUUUCUGGUUCCUUUAACAGCAAAAGGAAAGAGAGGUUCUGAUUCUUACCUCAGGGUUUUUUGGUUGUUCAUUGUUUUUGUUUUUGUUUUUGUUUUGACACUGCAGAGCACAAGGCUAAAGGUUACAGCUGAGAUCUUUGGAACCAAAGGCAGAGCAAGCAGAGCCCGUUGUCUGGGCCCCACACCACUGCAGGCAGGUGGAUAGAAGUGCGGCCCCUCUCAUAGUAUGCCCAUAAGUCAGGGCAUAGGGCAGAACUACCUGUCAUGUUGCUACACCAUCCUGUCUUCUCAGCAUCUCCUUGCCUGUUUUCUUUAUUAGUCCAAAGGAAAACAACAGCAACAAAAUCUGUUUUUAAAAUGUCUUAUAUGAACAUAUAUCAAAUAUCCAUGCGCUGAAACCCACAUACCAUCACUUGGCAAUUUUUUAGAAUAAGACCCCAUUAUUAUCUAUUGCUAUAAACCUAGCCAGUUCUCUUGCUCUUCUGUAUUUUCCUAUUUCCCUGCCAUCAUCUGCUAUUUCUGCCACUUCUCUUAGACUCCUUGUCUGCAAAGCCCAAGCUAGAACUCACUGUCUAUGGCAGAAGGACAUCCAGAGCCCAUUCUGGAGUUUUGUUUUUUCCUUCUGCCAGAUGCUUUGUGUCCUGUCUUCCUUCCUCCUCAUAUUUCUGUUUCUCAUUUGUGUUCAGUUUUGUGCAGCAUUGCUAGCACUGCUUUUGUGACCAGAAAAGGCCAUAACAUGGUCCAGGAUCAUCAUUCUUCUGACUCUAGAUGGGACACUUGACAGUGACUUGAAACAUUUGCAUAUUCAGGAAUGCAUGAGAUUUCAAGAGAGCCUACAGUAUGAAAUCAUUUUCACAAAAUAAGCAGCUUGCUUCUGAAAUGCUGUCUUUCCCAGUAGCUACUCACCUGCCUCUGGUGGCUGGGAUUCAGAUGCCACAAAACUGUCAGUAUCUAUAGACCAGGUCUGUGCCACCUCCUCUCUCCUCUGUGCUCAGUGAGGAGGCAGUAAAUGAAGUUACAGGCUAGCACAAUACCUAACUCAUGUUUCCCAGUACACCUGUAGAUAUUACUGUACUUUUAUGUUCUCAAGAAAUAAGUUGUUGCCUAUUCAGUGUUACAGAUUUCUUUGUUUCUUUUUAAUUAAAAUACAAGAAGCAGCUGAGGAAAGGGAGACAAGGUAUUUUAUUUCUGACUGAUUUUAGAAAAAACUUGUGUACAUGUGUUUGGAACUGUUGAAAUGCCAAGUUUUCUGUAUAAGUGUUUUUGUAAUUAAACUUUCAGAUUUUCUUUGUUUUUUAAGAAGUUGAUGUGCUUGUUUGACAUUUGUCUCAUUAAAACUUUUCUACGUUGAA